AUGAUAGCAGAUGUUAAAGAUAUUGGAAACAGUGCAAUUUCUCCUAGUGUAGAAGGAGGAGGAACCUUGCAGCAAUCCAGCAGUUGCAGUCGGGUCUCCUUUCUAACAAAUCCUAAAGGGCAGCCAUCUUGCUUCCUUCUGCUUCUCUACGAAAGCAGCCUAGCCUCCGCAUCAAUAUUCAUAAGGCAGUUUGACGUCUGUUCUCAUCACUCAGCGGGGCCGGCGUCUCGGGGCGGCCGCGCCGAGGGGGCGGACGUGACUUGCAUGCGAGCGGGACCCGGGCGCGCGGCGCUCGCGAGGAGGCGGCGGCGGCCGCCCAAGCUCUCGCCGCUGCCACUGCCGCUACCGCCGGCUCUCCUCCUCCGCCCGGGCCUCCUCCUGCUCCGCCCCGGCCUCCUCCCGCUCCGCCCCGGCCUGCGCCGCCGCCCUGGGGCCCUCAGCCCCGGCUCCCAGGGAAUUAGCCCCCCGCACCGGGCGUCCAGCACAAAGGCCGGCGGCACCUGGGGCCGUACAGCGGGGCGCGCAGUGGAGACCUGGGCUGCCCUCACGCCGUGCAGUGGCGCGGGGGGAGUGGUGCGCCCGGACCAGCGCGGAGUAGGGGCCAGGGCUGGCGAGCGCGGGGAAGGGUGCAGCCCUCGGGAACCCCGGGGACCUCGGCGGGUCUCCACCCCUGGGAGAAGAAGCAGAGCAAGCGCGAAGGUUGGGGGCGAGGUGGGAGGUUGGGAUGGCACGGGUGCCUGGACAAAGACGUGACAUCUAAGAUUUCCCUUUGAAACUUUUUGCUGGUCUGCACUCCACCACCACUUCGAGGUCCCGCGCACACGCCCCCGCGCGCACCCACCUCCUCCGGAGUGUACCCGCACGUGCCCUCGCUCUGGCCCCCGCCUCCACCCACUGGCACCUCUCCCCGCACCACACCUCCGCUUGCGCCCACCUUACCCUCAGAGGCCCGCGUCUCUAUCUCCCUUUAGAUCCCGUUGCCCGCGCUCUCCUUUCCCUUUUCUGUCGCUUUAAUCUCAUUCAGCAGAAGCGCUCCCCUGUUUCACCGAGGGCAUGCCCUUAGUGCUUUAGGGGCCUGUAUUUUUAAAGACCCGACAAACUGGGAAAUUGACCGAGUUCUGUUUCUCCCCGCCCCGGCCCACCUUCUGUUUACUUUAGCCACGUGGGCUGAGUAGAAGGGGGCGUCUCACAGAUUGAAAUAGGUUUCUCACUAGUGACCCCCUACUUCUCGCUAGGAGGAAAUAAACCUGCACUUUCAAAUGCUUAAGUUGCCUCUCGUAAGAGCCCUUACUUUGAAGUAGUUUCCCCCCGUACAAUUAAGUAAUGAAGAAACCGACCGAUACAGAGCUAAUUCCGAAUGACGGAUGCUUGAUUUUCCCUGACAUUCGGAGCUCUGUAACUAUGCUCUUCCUUUGACCGGAGUUUUUCUCUAUUGCCGAGUAGUGUUACUUCCCCCUUCUAAUGCUCCUUUUUCUAAUCAUCAACUUUUUAUUUGAAGAUGAGAUGAAGAACAAAGCCCAUAUGAGUCAUAAGAGACAGUUUAAUCAGUCCGUGACCAAAAUCAAACAGAGUAAACUGUGUCAUCAUGGAGAUCUGCCCAGGAAAUCCCCAAAAUACAGAAGGAUCAGAAGUAGAUGGAAAUAAUGUCAUAGAACGUCUCUCACAACUGUGUUAUAAGAAUGACAGGGAAGCUACAGGUUACAACAGAUUUGUGAACUCAGCCAAGCACAGUGGUGGCAGGGCCUAGCUGCUACAAAGAAGACAUGUUUUAGACAAAUACUCAUGUGUAUGGGCAAAAAACUCGAGGACUGUAUUUGUGACUAAUUGUGUAACAGGGUAUUUUAGUUCCUGUUCUGUGGAAAGUGUAAAGCAUUCCAACAAAGGGUUUUAAUGUAGAUUUUUUUUUGCACCCAUGCUUUGAUUGCUAAAUGUAAUAGUCAGAUCGUGACGCUGAAUAAAUGUCUUUUUCUAAAAAAAAAAAAAAAGAA